CUCCUGGGCUCAAGUGAUCCUCCCACCUCAGCCUCCCAAAGUGCUGGGACUACAAGCAUGAGCCACUGUGCAGGGCCAACAAUAGAUUGUCAGUGUAAAUAAAACAGCCUUCUAUUGUAAGAAGAUGCCAUUAGAACUUUCAUUGCUAGAGGGGAAAAGCCAAUAUUUGGCUUAAAAUCUUCAAAAGACAGGCUGACUUUCUUGUUAGGGCUAAUGCAGCUGGUGACUUUAAGUGGAAGCCAGUGCUCAUUACUAUACUGAAAAUCACAGGGUCCUUAGGAAUUAUGCUACAUCUACUUCUCUGCCUGUGCUCUAGAAACGUAACAACAAAGCCUGGAUGACAGCACGUCUGUUUACAGCAUGAUUUACAGAAUAUUUUAAGCCCACUGUGGGGACCUGCUGCUCAGGAAAAAAAAUAUUUCUUUCAAGAUAUUACUGUUGAUUGACAAGGCACCUGGUCACCCAAGAGCUCUGAUGGAGAUGUGCAAAGAGAUUGAUGCUGUUUUCCUGCAUGCUUGCAUCUAUUCUGCAGCCCGUGGAUCAAAGGGAUCUUGGAGUGAAAAUAUACUGGAAUAUUUUCUGAGAAAUAGCCAGAUUACAGCAGAAGACGGUGCUGAGAUCACCUGGUAUCAUGCAGCUAACCACAAGGCACAAACAAAUGAGGCACUGAAAAGUACUGCUCACAUGAUAGAGGCUGAUGUCCUUCUUCCAAGUGAUGGAUCAGAACACAGCCAGCCAAUUAUGGCCCAUCCCCCUGAAACAAACAGUGAUAAUACUCUACAGGAGUGGCUGACUGAAGUUAUGAAAAGCAAUAAAGGCAUCAAGCUGGAUUUCAAAAGUCUGGCAGUUGUAGAACCAUCCAUGAUGCUCUUGGAAAAUGUGAAGAGGCAUCUGAAGCGUCCUGUAUGGAUUAAUGCCGAUAUUCUUCCUGGUCCAAAUGGAAAUAGCAAAGUAAUAGAUGCAAAACCAUUUUUAGACACCGUGAUAUCCUUCUUUCCAGACGUGACGUUUUCCCUGGGUUGGACAACAGGAUGGCAUCCUGAGAAAGUCAAUGAAGGGUACAGUUGGACAAUGGUGAAAGAGAUGGAAUAUAUAUGUAAUGAACUAAGUCAGCCUGUAACGUUCCCUGUCAGAGCAGCAUUAGUCAGGCAGUCUUGUUCUCAGUUACUUUGGCUGUUAAAGAAAUCAAACAGGUACAGCCUGACUAUUUGGACUGGAAAAAAUGAUAACUAUUCCGUUGAAGAUUUACUUUACAUUAGAGACCAUUUUGACAAAAAACAAGUUUUCUAUGACAUCUUGGAACCACAAAACCAUGAAUUUAAACAAGCCAUUGGAAUCAAAGUUAAUCUCUAAGAAGAAGAUUCUCAAUUAUUUCCUGUGUUUUGGUUUCAUAAUCCUUCUCUCCAUUGGUCUGAAUUAAUUACCAUAUAAAUUAUGGUUAUUGAUUGACGUUCCAAGUCAUCUAAUCAAGAAACGUUUAUUGUAUGCUUACUCUGUGGGCAUAUGUCCUUAUAAUAGUGCACUUACAUAAAAGAUUUGGAAAGAAGAGAUUUAUUUACACACGUGGCCUAGUCUAAUAAUAAUUCAGGAAAAUGAUACUCUGCACCCCUUCAUAAAAAUAGUUUUGAUAAACUAAAGAUGAUUGGCAGAAUCCAUAUGUCAUAAAACAGGUAUAAAUCACAUGUGCUUGGCACUUGCAUUACAGAGAUUAUGAAAAAUAUGGUACUCUUUUCCUUUUUCCUAGAAAACUGGUUAUUUUAGAGAUAACAAAAAAGGAAGAGGGCUUUUAAAAUGUUUUUAAUUUUCACAGGGGUCAGCAGCUGUCUCAUAUCAAGAUCUAUUAAUCCAUUUCCUGAAACUGUAGAUUAAAUUAGAUAGAUCUAGAAUUUCCAUGUGAUUGAGAAGCAUGCUAGUGGCUAAGUGUUUUUUUUAUAUUUCUUAUUUCUAUAGUAUCUGAUUUAUAGUGGACAAUAUACUGUUGGAGAGCAGUUUUAGUCUUUGUUAUGUAUCAUUUGUUUUCCAAGUUUCUUACUGCCACCACCUUCAUUCAGGUCCUUGUUCUACUAGUAAAACUUUAUGAACUA